ACGCUACAGCGCGCGCCCGGCAGCUAGGCGCUGUGGUUUCUGGGUCUCCCGGGGGACCCCUACACGUUCCGGCAAAAAGCGCUCGUGCCCACCUCAAGCCCAUGUUCGGUGGGUGGCGAAUGCGUGCCCGUGAUCUGCUGGGUCUGUAGAGGAGCGCAGGCCUGGUGCAAACAGACUCAAGAGGCUCGGAGAACCAGCUUGGGUAGGCGCUUGGGUGAUGGAAGGUCAGGGGUCAGAGGUCGGGAGGGAGGGAGGGAGGUGGUCUUUGGCCUCCGGGACCAGGGAGGGAGGACGCUGGUUGUCCUGGAGCCCGGGAAGCUCAAGGGCUGAGAGGGAGCCGCUGCGCGAGUCUUCCCCACCUCUUCCCGAUCCCGGACUAGCGAACUUCGGACCACCACGUCCCUCCGGGGAUAAAGUGGGGUCGUGGGAAAGGAGGCUGUGCUUCUCCUCAUGCACUGGGGCCUGCGGUGUUUGUCUCGAGCGUCCAACACACUAGGAUCCGGGAGUCCGUCGUCACGCUCCUUGGCCUCGCGGUCGCUUGUUUGCUCGGCCUGCUGGGAGCGAUCCGGCGCUGACAGCCCCGCUCAGACUCCGGGAGCCGCUUGUGGGUCUUUCGGAAGAUAACUGAAGUUCACAGUUACCAGCCAAGAAAACUUGAAAAUGAGCAGCCGACGGAAACGUGCUCCUCCAGUGAGGGUAGAUGAGGAAAAGAGGCAGCAGCUUCAUUGGAAUAUGCAUGAGGACAGAAGGAAUGAACCUAUCAUCAUAAGUGAUGAUGACGAGCAGCCCUGCCCAGGUUCAGAUACCUCUUCUGCUCAUUAUAUCAUUCUAAGUGAUAGUCUAAAGGAAGAAGUGGCUCACAGAGAUAAGAAGAGGUGUUCAAAAGUGGUGAGCUUCUCAAAACCAAUUGAAAAAGAAGAGACUGUUGGUAUUUUUUCCCCUUUGUCUGUAAAGUUAAAUAUUGUGAUUUCUCCCUAUCAUUUUGAUAAUUCCUGGAAAGCAUUUCUAGGAGAAUUAACUCUUCAGCUUCUUCCUGCACAGAGUUUAAUUGAAAAUUUUUCCGAAAGGAGUAUUACAUUGAUGAGUUCAGAGUCAAGCAAUCAGUUCCUGAUUUAUGUUCAUUCAAAAGGUGAAGAUGUAGAGAAACAAAAAAAAGAACCGAUGAGUAUUUGUGACAAGGGUAUUCUGGUGGAGUCAUCCUUCAGUGGUGAAAUGUUAGAAGAUUUGGGGUGGCUACAAAAGAAGAGAAGAAUAAAACUCUAUCAGAAACCAGAAGGAAAUCACAUUAUCAAGGUUGGAAUUUAUCUUUUGGAAGCUGGCCUAGCAAAACUAGACUUCUUGAGUGAUGCAAAUUCAAGAAUGAAAAAGUUCAAUCAGCUCAUGAAGAAAGUAAUGGAAAAGUUACACAAUUCUAUUAUUCCAGAUGUGUUGGAAGAGGAUGAAGAUGAUCCGGAGAGUGAGCCAGAGGGACAAGACAUUGACGAGCUGUAUCACUUUGUGAAACAAACACAUCAGCAAGAAACGCAGUCCAUCCAAGUGGAUGUCCAGCAUCCUGCAUUGAUCCCUGUGUUGAGACCCUACCAAAGAGAGGCUGUCAAUUGGAUGCUACAACAAGAGUGUUUCAGAAGCAGUCCUGCUACUGAAAGUGCCCUGCACUUCUUAUGGCGAGAGAUUGUUACAUCUGAGGGUCUGAAACUCUACUAUAAUCCAUAUACAGGCUGCAUCAUUCGUGAGUACCCAAAUUCUGGGCCGCAGUUGCUUGGUGGAAUUUUAGCAGAUGAGAUGGGUCUUGGAAAGACAGUGGAGGUUUUGGCUCUGAUUCUGACACAUACUCGACAAGAUGUCAAGCAAGAUGCUCUCACUCUUCCCGAGGGAAAAGUGGUGAAUUAUUUUAUUCCGUCACAUUAUUUUGGAGGAAAACUGAAAAAGACAGAAAUCCAGAAUAUCGAAUUUGAACCAAAAGAAAAAGUUCAAUGCCCUCCUACACGUGUGAUGAUACUGACAGCUGUGAAAGAAAUGAAUGGAAAAAAAGGAGUGUCCAUCCUUUCCAUCUAUAAGUAUGUCAGUUCUAUAUAUAGAUACGAUGUUCAACGGAACAGGAGUCUUUUGAAACGGAUGCUGAAAUGUUUAAUUUUUGAAGGUCUCGUGAAACAGAUCAAAGGCCAUGGUUUUUCUGGGACUUUUACAUUGGGAAAGAAUUACAAGGAAGAGGAUAUAUGUGAUAAAACAAAAAAGCAGGCAGUAGGGAGUCCAAGGAAAAUUCAGAAAGAAACUAGAAAAUCAGGGAACAAGGACACAGAUUCUGAAUACUUGCCAUCAGACACCUCUGAUGAUGAUGAUGAUCCUUACUAUUAUUAUUAUAAGUCCAGGAGAAAUCGCAGUAAAUUGAGGAAAAAGCUUGUUCCAUCCACAAAAAAAGGAAAAAGUCAACCAUUUAUCAAUCCCGAUUCACAAGGUCACUGUCCAGCUACUAGCGACUCUGGAAUAACUGAUGUUGCUAUGUCUAAAAGUACAUGUAUCUCUGAAUUCAACCAAGAACAUGAAACAGAGGACUGUGCUGAAUCUCUAAAUCAUGCUGAUAGUGAUGUACCACCUUCUAAUACCAUGAGUCCCUUUAACACCUCUGAUUACCGCUUUGAGUGUAUAUGUGGUGAACUUGAUCAGAUAGAUCGUAAGCCUCGUGUUCAAUGCCUGAAGUGUCACCUGUGGCAACAUGCAAAGUGUGUGAAUUAUGAUGAGAAAAAUCUGAAGAUCAAGCCUUUUUACUGCCCCCACUGCCUUGUUGCAAUGGAACCAGUGUCAACAAGAGCAACUCUGAUCAUCUCUCCAAGUUCCAUCUGUCACCAGUGGGUGGAUGAGAUCAACAGGCAUGUGAGGUCGUCAUCUCUUCGAGUCUUGGUAUAUCAAGGAGUGAAGAAAGAUGGCUUUUUACAACCUCAUUUUUUGGCAGAACAGGAUAUAGUUAUCAUUACCUAUGAUGUACUGCGUUCAGAAUUAAAUUAUGUCGAUAUCCCACAUAGCAAUAGUGAGGAUGGGCGUCGCCUACGGAACCAGAAGCGCUAUAUGGCUAUCCCGAGCCCCCUGGUAGCUGUGGAGUGGUGGAGGAUCUGCCUUGAUGAAGCUCAGAUGGUUGAGUGUCCCACAGUAAAAGCUGCAGAAAUGGCCCAGCGUUUGAGUGGGAUUAAUCGAUGGUGUAUCAGUGGCACUCCAGUACAGAGAGGAUUAGAGGAUCUUUUUGGGUUAGUGGUCUUUCUUGGUAUUGAACCUUACUGUGUCAAACACUGGUGGGUUCGACUUCUCUAUCGGCCUUACUGCAAGAAGAAUCCUCAGCAUCUCUACAGCUUUAUUGCCAAGAUACUGUGGAGGUCUGCAAAGAAAGAUGUGAUUGACCAAAUCCAAAUACCACCACAAACCGAAGAAAUACACUGGCUCCACUUUUCUCCAGUGGAAAGGCAUUUCUAUCACCGUCAGCAUGAGGUGUGCUGCCAGGAUGUGGUGGUAAAACUCAGGAAGAUUUCUGACUGGGCUCUGAAGCUCAGCAGCCUAGACAGAAGGACUGUCACCUCUAUCCUGUAUCCAUUGCUGAGGCUCAGACAGGCCUGCUGUCACCCACAGGCUGUUCGUGGAGAGUUCUUGCCACUCCAAAAAAGCACCAUGACAAUGGAAGAGCUGCUGACAUCUUUGCAGAAGAAAUGUGGAACUGAAUGUGAAGAAGCACAUCGACAGCUAGUUUGUGCUCUCAAUGGCUUAGCAGGCAUUCAUAUUAUUAAAGGUGAGUAUGCCUUGGCAGCAGAAUUGUACAGAGAAGUGUUGCGCUCCUCGGAGGAACACAAAGGAAAACUCAAAACUGAUUCACUUCAAAGACUUCAUGCUACCCAUAACUUGAUGGAAUUGUUGAUAGCCAGGCACCCAGGGAUACCACCUACCUUGCGUGAUGGCCGACUUGAGGAAGAGGCCAAACAGCUGCGAGAGCACUACAUGAGCAAGUGUAAUACAGAAGUUGCUGAAGCCCAGCAAGCUUUAUAUCCUGUGCAGCAGACCAUCCAUGAGCUUCAAAGAAAGAUUCAUUCUAAUUCUCCUUGGUGGCUAAAUGUGAUCCACAGAGCAAUAGAAUUUACUAUUGAUGAGGAGCUAGUUCAGCGAGUGCGAAAUGAAAUAACCAGCAACUACAAGCAACAAACUGGCAAGCUUUCUAUGUCAGAGAAGUUCCGUGAUUGCAGAGGUCUUCAGUUCUUACUUACAACACAAAUGGAAGAGCUAAAUAAAUGCCAGAAGCUAGUAAGAGAGGCUGUAAAAAACCUGGAGGGACCUCCAUCUCGUAAUGUUAUUGAGUCUGCAACAGUCUGUCACCUCCGACCAGCCAGACUUCCUCUCAACUGCUGUGUCUUUUGUAAAGCUGAUGAAUUGUUCACAGAGUAUGAAUCAAAGCUAUUUUCCAACACAGUCAAAGGCCAGACUGCAAUAUUUGAGGAGAUGAUAGAAGAUGAAGAAGGACUGGUGGAUGAUCGAGCACCUACCACCACCCGGGGUCUCUGGGCAAUAAGUGAGACAGAGCGAUCUAUGAAAGCAAUACUAUCAUUUGCAAAAUCACAUAGGUUUGAUGUUGAAUUUGUUGAUGAAGGAAGCACUUCAAUGGAUCUCUUUGAAGCAUGGAAGAAGGAAUAUAAGUUGCUUCAUGAAUAUUGGAUGGCUCUGAGGAAUCGUGUGUCUGCUGUUGAUGAACUUGCAAUGGCUACAGAACGACUAAGAGUGCGUGAUCCUAGGGAGCCAAAGCCUAAUCCGCCUGUUCUUCAUAUCAUUGAACCACAUGAGGUAGAACAAAACCGAAUAAAACUACUAAAUGAUAAAGCUGUUGCUACAUCACAGCUUCAGAAAAAACUUGGGCAGCUUCUUUACCUAACUAAUUUGGAGAAGUCUCAAGAUAAAACAUCGGGAGGUGUUAAUCCAGAACCUUGCCCAAUCUGUGCUCGACAGCUAGGAAAACAGUGGGCGGUACUGACCUGUGGUCACUGUUUCUGUAAUGAAUGCAUUUCUAUAAUUAUUGAACAAUACAGCGUGGGAUCUCACAGAAGCUCCAUUAAGUGUGCAAUCUGCCGCCAGACCACAUCUCACAAAGAAAUCUCGUAUGUCUUUACCUCAGAGAAAGCAAACCAGGAGGAGGACAUCCCUGUGAAGGGCAGCCAUUCUACAAAAGUGGAAGCUGUGGUCAGAACUCUGAUGAAAAUACAGCUUAGAGAUCCAGGGGCCAAAGCACUCGUUUUCUCAACGUGGCAAGAUGUAUUAGAUAUUAUUUCAAAAGCUCUUACUGACAACAACAUGGAAUUUGCACAAAUCAGUCGUGUUAAGACAUUUCAGGAGAACCUUUCAGCAUUUAAACGUGAUCCCCAAAUCAAUAUUUUGCUGCUGCCCCUGCACACAGGUUCUAAUGGAUUAACUAUCAUUGAAGCAACUCAUGUUCUCUUGGUGGAGCCCAUAUUGAACCCUGCCCAUGAGCUUCAGGCCAUAGGGAGGGUGCACCGAAUUGGACAGACAAAACCUACUAUUGUACACAGAUUCUUAAUUAAAGCAACAAUAGAAGAAAGAAUGCAGGCAAUGCUGAAAACUGCUGAGAGAAGGUAUUGGAAAAAGCAGUUUAUCCACCAUCAUUACAUAAAAAGGACGCUUAUCAGACCAAGCAUUCCUAACUGGAGUCAGUGGACUUACGAAAGGAAAAAAGGUCCACAGGUGAGCUUCAAAGGGCAAACUCCCAAGAUGUGUACCUUCCAGCAGCUUCCUAGAGACAGAGUUUCAUAUUGUCAGAUUCUUAAAGGGAUUCAAGGCCUAAAAGGACCCAUUGCCAUAGACCAUCAGUUUCCAAGUGUGGUCCUUAGGGAUCUCCAAGACCAAGGAGUCUGAAGGGCCCUAGGAUUUUCUUCAUAUGUGUCAACAAAAACAACAUGCUCAACACAAGUCUCUUGCCUGCCACCAUGUAAGACAUGCCUUUGCUCCUCCUUCACCUUCAACCCUAAUUGUGAGGCCUCCCCAGCCAUGAGGAACUGUAAGUUAAUUCAACCUCUUUUUCAUUAUAAAUUACCCAGUCUUGGGGAUUUCUUCAUAAGAGUAUGAAAAUGGACUAAUACAAACAACAACAAAGAAUUUAAAUAAUGAAAUAUAUUCCAUAGCCUGUUUUUAUUUAAAAACUAAAAAUCUAUGUUUUAAUAACAGCAAAAAGAUUCUGUCCCAUUAGUAAGUAAAAACACAAUCUUUUACAUUGUUUUACUCCAACUAUAAUUUAUGCGUGCUUUAAAAUAGAAAUAGCUAAUAACCUAUUUACAUUUUAAAUAAAUGUGCACUGGAUAUAUAGUUGCACAAACCUUUUACUGGUGAGAUAUGUAAUUAAAUAAGUUUGGAGAUCACUGGAAGAGAAGUAAUUGUUGCUCUUACGAAUGUGAGAAGCUUUUAUUCUAGUUAAGUUUUUAUCACUCGAAACUCUUUUAGGAUGCUUGAAAUUGCUUUCAAAGCCAAUUAAGAAAUUAUACAAUUUCUUCAUAACCUCACAUCAUUUUGUUUUAUUAACCAAAAAAGUAUAUUUUCUAUUUUAUAUACAUUAACUUAUUAUAUUUUGUAAUGUAUAUAUUUUAUAUAGUUUCUAAUUUAUACUCAUUACGUGCCAGGCUUGCUUUGCAUGUGUACCCUUCCUGAAAAGUUUUUUUCUUUCCUUUUCAACUUUUUUUUUUUUUCUUUGAGACAAGAUCUCACUGUGUUACCCACGUUGGAGUGCAUUGGCAUGAUCAUGACUCACUGCAGCCUCAACCUCCCAGGGUCUGGUGAUCUUCCCACCUCAAUCUCCCAGGUAUCUGGAACUGCAGGCACAUGCCACCACACUAGGAUGAUUUUUGUAGUUUUUGUAGAGACAGGGUUUCUCCAUGUUGCCCAAGCUGGUCUCAAACUCCUGGGCUCAAGUGAUCCUCCUGCCUCAGCCUCCCAAAGUGCUAAGAUUACAGGCAUGAGCCACUGCACUCAGCCUGUAUUUUUAAUCUUAAAAUUGGCAGUUAUGGGUCAAGAAUUUUGCAGAGGAAAUGUAGACCUAUGUUAAUAUUAAAUAAUGAAUUUAUUCCAUGUUUCAAUUUUUUCAGUCAAAAAGUAGAUAAAGCACCUAAUUUAGGCUUAAUAAUAAUUUAUUAUCUCAUGAAGUUUCUAGAAUGUUUGGAGAUACACCUGGUAACAUGAGGGAAAAAGUCAACAGUAAAUGUUCUGUUUUCAGAAACCUAAACAUUGAGAAAAUUAAUAUUGUCAACAAAUGUUAGUACUUAGUCUUGUGUCUUGCAAUAUUUUCAUGUUUGUUUUCUCCCUCAUUGGGUAGAGAAGGCGUGAAGAAUUUCAUCAUUAUAUCAAGAUGGUGGGGGGAAGCUAGUCACCAUUUCUUUUUUUCUUUUUUCCUUUUUUUUUUUUUUUUUUUUUUGAGAUUGAGUUUCACUCGUUACCCAGGCUGGAGUGCAAUGGUGCGAUCUUGGCUCACCACAACCUCCUACUCCCGGGUUCCAGCAAUUCUCCUGCCUCAGCCUCCCGAGUAGCUGGCAUUACAAGGCACCCACCACCAUGCCCAGAUAAUGUUUGUAUUUUUAGUAAACACGGGGUUUCACCAUGUUGGCCAGGCUGGUCUCGAACUCCUGACCUCAGGAGAUCCACCUGCCUUGGCCUCCCAAAGUGCUGGGAUUACAGGCAUGAGCCACCACACCCGGCUGCUAGUCACCUUUUCUACUGAAUACAGAAGAGGCGCCUAUAGGAUCGGUUUUGAUUAUCCAUGAGAAAAGAGAGUUUUAGAAUGCAGAAUAAACUAUCAAAGGAGAUAGUGAAAUCCUUUCUGAAAAAUUUUAAGAAAAGGAAAGAAUUUUUUUAAGUGCAGAUAAACUUCAAGAGUUUAAGUCCUAUAUUUAAAUAACUAUGGUAUUUUCUGUUUUAGGUUUGUUUUUCUUUCUCCCAAAAUAUAUGGUGUUAAGUUCCAGAAUAUCUUCAGCCAACUAAGAAAUACAAGGAGGAAUGGGGGGUGUUAUUUUCUUUUUUUUUAAAGUUAGUAAACAGAGAAAAAGCAACUAUUUCUUUUUUAAAAUGUAUCAAAGAAUUUAAUGACUUCAGUACAAGAGGCAGUGGGUGUUCAGUAAAUAGUAAUUUAACUGGUUAGAAUAAAUAAAAAUAUGAUAACUAUGGCUCACAACAGAGCAGAGUCAUGUAGUUACUAAAACAUUUGCACAAAUACUGUCCACCAAAGGGACCCAGCUCAUAAGCACUGAGAAAUGACUAAUAUUUCUCAUGUAACUGUAUUAUUCCCAUCUGUUUCAUAUUUAAAUUUAGAGGAAGUUUUAAUAGUACCAAAUUCAUAUAAAUCUUUUGAAGUCCAUGAACAGUAAGAAGUGCUAUUUGAUUCUUAUUCCUUGAUUUUGAUAUCAGUAAUUGUUAUACACACUGAUUAGCUUUUAUCUCCAAAUUUUAUUUAAUACUGCCUAAUGCUGGUUGUUUCUUUUGGAGUCCUAUAAAUCUGGCUGCCAAGAAAAAUGAUGGCUCUGCUCCGAAACCACAAAGUGGCUGUAUUAACAUUUAGUGAAUCUCAAGUAGAAAGGAACAGUGAAAUUCCUGAGGAAGCCAUUCUCCAGAAUAAUAAAGUAUUAGCGUUUUUCUCAUAGUAGACAAAAGUCAUGGGUUUUCCUCCUUGGCAGGGAGCAAACUCAACCUUAAAAAGUGAUAGUCAACAACAGAAAGACAAAUAACCCAAUUUAAAACUGGGCAAAGGAUUUGAAUAGACAUUUCUCCAAAGAAGAUAAUAUGUAAGUGACCAAUAAGCACAUGAAAAGAUGAUCAACAGCUUUAGCAGCUGGGAAAGUAGAUAUCAAAACCGAAAUAUGAAGGUUUGGAGAGGAGGAAGGAAUGAAUAAACAAAACGGGAUUUUUAGGACAGUGAGCCUUCUGUAUGCUACUACACGGGUGGAUAUAUGUCAUUACACAUUUGCUGGACCCAUAGAAUGUACAACACCAAAAAUGGACCCUAAUAUAAACUGUGGACUUUGGAUAAUGAUGUGUCAUAAUUUGAAACAAAUGUACAACUGUGAUGUGGGAUAUUGAUAGUAGGAAAGGUUGUGCAUGGGGUUGGGGGGAGGCAGGGGUAUAUGAGAACUCUGUGUACUUUCUGCUCAAUUUUGCUGUGAACCUAAAACUUUCGUAGAAAAUAGUCUAUUAGAAAACAAUGAGCUAUCACUUUACACCACAUGACUUGUAGAUGAAAAGAGUCAAACUCUGUAAAAUAUUUGAAGAGAUUUAUUCUGAGUCAAAUAUGAACAACCUUGGCCCGUGACACAGCCCUCAGGUGGUCCUGAGAACAUGUGCCCAAGGUGGUCGGGGUGCAGCUUGGUUUUAUAUAUUUUAGAGAGGCAUAAAACAUCAAUCAAAUACAUUUAAGAAAUACAUUGGUUUGGUUCAGAAAGGUGAGACAACUCAAAGUGGGGCCUUCCAGGCUAUAGGUAAAUUUAAACAUUUUCGGGUGGACAGUUGGUUGAAUUUGUCUAAAGACUUGGGAUCAAUAGAAAGGAAUGUUCAGGUUAAGAUAAAGGAUUGUGGAGAACCAGUUUUAUUGUUCAGAAGAAUCUCUCAGAUGGCAGACUUCAGAGAGAGGGUAGGUUGUAAAAUGUUUCUUAUCAAAUCUAAAAGGAUGCCUAGCUCUUAGUUGAUUAUCCACUGGAUCUGCAAAGAAAGGAAAGAAAAUAAAAGGGGAAGGAGAUUUUCUAUGGAAUGUGGAUUUUUCCCACAAGAGACUUUGCAGGGCAAUUUCGAGGCAUGGCAAGGAAAUAUAUUAUGGGGCUAAAUAUUAUUUCCUUGUCUCAUAAUGUCACGCCAGAGUCAGAUUGAAAAGCAAGUCACAAUAUACAUGGUCAAAUAAAAGCCAUCUGAUGAGGAUCCAUGGUUUGUAGGACAUGACUCCCCAGACCUCUUAGGUAGGAAUUUGGGCAAGAUAAAAAUCAGAGCUUAGUCCCUGAACUAUAGUCAAAAGAUAGACAAUAACAAGUUUUGUUAAGGAUACAGAAAAUUGGAACCCUCAAACAUUGCUGGUAGGAAUGUAAAAUGGUACAGCUGCUUUGGAAAACCAUUUAUCCGUGUCUUAAAUAGUUAAAUGUACACCUAGCAGCUAUGCCACUCCUAUGUACUUAAGAGAAAAUAAAACAUAUAUUCAUACAAAAACUCAUAUGAACAGUCUGGCAGGUACCUGGAGUGUUAAAUGGAGUUACCACAUGACCCAACAUUUCUACUCCUAGGUAUUUACCUGUAAUAGUCUGCUAGAGCUGCCAUAACAAAAUACCACAGACUGAGUAAAUUAAACAACAGAAAUUUAUUUAUUACAGUUUUGGAGCCUGGCAGUUGAAGAUUACAGUGCUGGCAGGUCUGUUUUCUUCUAAGAUCUCUCUCCUUUCUUGCAGAUGGUUGUUUUCUGUAUCCUCACAUGGUGUUUCCCUGUGCGGACAGGCCCCUGAUGGCUUUUUAUAAGGACACUAUUCAUACGGGAUUAGAGCCCCCAUCCUAGCAGCUUUACUUUAGCAUAACCACCUCUAUACACACCUUAUCUUUAAAUACAGUUACAUCCUGAGAUACUAGGGGUUGGGACUUCAAAUUAUGAAUUUGGUGGAGCCACAGUUCAGCCUAUAAUAAUAAUGGAGAGAAAUGAAAACAUGUGUUCACAGAAAAACUUGUAUGUGAAUAUUUAUAGCAGCAUUAUUUAUAGUAGGCAAAUGUGGAAACAACCCAAAUGCCUAUCAAACGAUAAAUGGAUAAAUCAAAUAUGGUUAUACUUCUAAUGGAAUAUGAUUUGGACAAAAAAGAAAUGAAAUACUUAUACAUGCUACAACAUGGAUGAACCUUAAAAACAUUAUGCUAAGUGAAAAAAAGCAGUCCCAAAAUACUGUAUAUUUCUGUUUAUAAGAAAUGUCUAGAAUAGGCAAAUCUUUAUUUUUUUUAGAGGAUGGGUUCUCACUCUGUCACCCAGAUGGGAGUGCAGUAGCAGUAUCAUAAUUCACUGCAGCCUGAAACUCCUGGGCUUAAAUGAUCCUCCUGCCUUGGCCUCCUCAAGUAGCUGGGACUACAGGUGUACACCGCCACUCCUCAUAAGAACAGGCAAAUCUUUAGAGACAGAAAUUACAUUAGUGGUUGCCCAGGACUAGGAGAGGAACUGGAGUGACUGCUAAUGGGCAUGGGGUUUCUUUAUGGAGUAAUGAAAGUGUUCUAAAUUUAGACUGUAGUGAUAGUUGCACAACUUUGUGAAUCUACUAAAAACCACUGACUUGUACACUUUAAAUGGCUGAAUUUCAUGGUGUGUGAAUUGUAUCUCGAAGAUAUUUUUGAAACAUUUUUAAAGUAGCACAAAAGCUUAUUUUAAAAAAUAUCAUUUGGCAUGCAAAACUUCGGCAGAGCCAAUUGUAGAUGAAAAUGAGACAGAUGGCCUUCAAAAUAUGAAGCACACAUUGUAAAGAAUGUUGUACUCCAGGCCUGUGAAUCUCACUGAUAUCUGGCAGCCACAGUUAAAAUGUUGUAGCAUCUGGAAUUGCGGGCUGUAAUUGAAACUCAACUGAAGAGCUUUCUGUGGAGCUGGAAUGACCAGCCAAUGCAUAAAGUUGUUAAACAUGAAACAAAGAUAACUAUUAUCUUUUAAAAACCUCUCAUUAACCCUCAUGACGUUCUUGGGUGAAGGUCUAAUCUGGCACACUUGCUAACUUCUAAUAAAGAAUCAAAUGGUCUUCCAACUCACAUAAUGACUAAUUCUAAAGCAUGCAACCUCAAAGUACUACAUUCUCCCUGUUCUAGAAAUACAACCCUAGAGGGCCAGUCUUCCUUCAGCAUUCAAAUAUUGAGUAGAACAACUGAACUGUAAGGUUCAACUAAAGGAAUGCAACUGUGACUUGAGCUGUGGAACGGCUAUGGCCUAAGUCAAGAAUUCUCAACCUCAGCACUAGUGAUUGACAUUUUGGGCCAGGCAAUUCUUUCUUCUGGGGCCUGUCCUAUGCAUUAUAAGAUUGAGCAGCAUCCCUGGCCUCUACCCAUUAGAUGCCAGAAACAUACUCCACCCCCAAGCUUUGACAACCAAAAAUGUUUCCAGAAAUUUCCAAUAUCUCCUGGGGCUUAAAUCAAGAACCACUGGCAUAAGCCAAGGAAGAACUAACCAUUUACCAUGGUACAGGAUGAGUAUCCCAUAUCUUGGGACCAGAAGUGUUUUGGAUUUCAGAUUUUUUAAUAUUUGCAUUAUGUGCUUACUGGUUGAGCAUCUGAAAUCCAAAAUGCAUUUCCCUUGAGACUUAUAUCAGUGCUCAAAAGGUUUCAGUUUUGAAGCAUUUCAAAUUUGGGAUUUUGGGAUUUGGGAUGCUAAUCUGCAAUAACAUAGACCAUGUACCAAAAGAAAAAAAUCGAUAUGUUUAAUUUGUACUUCAUUUAUUCAAGCUCUGUGGAGUUUAAAUAUUCAGAAUAUUAUGCAAAAACCAGUUUCCUUGAUCAUACUAAGUUUUGAUGACCAUAAUCAUUGACAAGUUUAUUCAGGAGAUUUUCAUAUGUUGCUCUAAAGUUUAAACCCAAUGCUGAAAUGCCAGCUUGGAGCCACAUAAGGAAUGAGCUGUUUGUAUUCUAUUAAAAGACUGCCCUUGAAAAUUUACAGAUGAAAAAACUUCAAGGGGAUAAAAAUGUGAUUUUAAAAUCAAUUUUGCCACCUAGUAAAGGAUUUGCUAAAUGGAUAACUAUGAGGUGAUGGAUGUGUUAAUUAUCUUGAUUUUGGUAAUCAUUUCAGAAUGUAUAUGUAUAUCAAAACAUUACAUUAUACACCUUAAAUAUGUACAAUUUUUGUAUGUCAAUUAUACCUUAAUAAAGCUCAGAAUAAAAAAAAAUGCUGUCAUUAACAGAGAGUUUGCAAAUACACUCAAAGUCUUUAUCAUUAAGGACACGGACACCAGGCAGCAUGAUGGAACUCACUUUCAUUGUUCUUCCAGCCUAUCAACUGAAUCACAUAAGAAUGAAAGAUGAAGUAAAGUUUUGAUACGGUGUACUUCAAGGUUUUUAAAUGUGAAUUUAUUGCAUUCUGAAACUAUGGUGUAGAUGACAUCUGCCCACACAUUAUUAUUAUUAUUAUUAUUAUUAUUAUUUUAUUAUUUUUGAGAUGGAGUUUCACUCUUGUUGCCCAGACUGGAGUGCAAUGGCACGAUCUCGGCUCACUGCAACCUCCUCUUCCUGAAUUCAAGUGAUUCUCCUGCCUCAGCCUCCCAAGUAGCUGGGAUUACAGGCUUGCUCCACCAUGCGCCGCUAAUUUUGUAUUUUUAAUAGAGACGGGGUUUCCCCAUGUUGGCCAGGCUGGUCUUGAACUCCUGACCUCAGGUGAUCCACCUGCCUCAGACUCCCAAAGUGCUGGGAUUACAGGCGUGAGCCACUGUGCCCAGCCUGCCCACACAUUUUGAUGUCAUAAUACUAACAUAAUAUCACUUUGUGAUAUUAAUUUUGUGACACUGAAAAGUCUUCACCUGUCUCAAGAGGACCCUAAGUAGACCUCAUGCCUCUGGCUUCUAGAGGCUGGGACUACAUAGUUUCUAACUUUUCGUUCUUUUUCUUCAUCCUCUCCCUCCCUCCCUCCCUCCCUCCCUCCCUUCCUUCCUUCCUUCCUUCCUCUAGCAACUGUUACUGAGACACUAAAACUGACAUCAUCAUUGACACUUAGCAAUUACAGUAUGCUGCUGGGAAGCAUGGGCAUGCUGGUUUCUUCUCAUAGCAGGAAUGGGAGGCUUACCAGGAACCCUCCUCAGAAUUUAUGUCCAUGAUUUUGGCUACAGAUGACCAUUAAAGCAGUAUAAGGUCAUAACCAGUAAAGUCUUCUCCUGUAACUUUCAGAAAAUAAAGUGAACUUAUUAACUGGAA